AGCCCGCUGGACGCGGGGCCGAGGGCGCGGACGCCGACGGGUCCGGGGCCGCGCGCUCCAGGGAAGCCUGCAUCCCGCUCCCCUGGGCCCCGACGGGCGGGCGCACUGCGCGGGGCCCACCGGCCGCAGACCUGCGUGGCCGUCCAGGGCGUCGCCAUGUCCUCGGUGUUUGGAAAACCCCGCGCGGGCAGCGGGCCUCAGAGCGCGCCCCUCGAGGUCAACCUGGCCAUCCUGGGGCGCCGCGGGGCUGGCAAGUCUGCCCUGACCGUGAAGUUUCUGACCAAGAGGUUUAUCAGUGAAUAUGACCCCAACUUGGAGGACACCUACAGCUCCGAGGAGACUGUGGACCACCAGCCUGUCCACCUGAGGGUCAUGGACACUGCAGACCUGGACACCCCCAGGAACUGCGAGCGCUACCUGAACUGGGCCCAUGCCUUCCUGGUGGUGUACAGCGUCGACAGCCGCCAGAGCUUUGAUAGCAGCAGCAGCUACCUGGAGCUGCUUGCCUUGCACGCGAAGGAGACACAGCGCAGCAUCCCUGCCCUGCUGCUGGGCAACAAGCUGGACAUGGCUCAGUACAGAUUGGUUUUAUUCAAGGUACCCCUAGACUUCCUGGCCAUAGUGGAGGGACCCAGCGGUGGUAAGCUGUCUGCCUAGAGAUUCUGACUGGGUCGUAGGGGGAACAGGUCUGCUGUACCCAUGGACAGCCACUCAUCUCUGAGUUGACUUUGCUGAGGUGCAUGUGUGCUGAUAGGGUGAGAGGGGCAAGCUCGCCUUCUGAAUGGCUACACUCCUCCAGGUCAUGCCUGCUUCCUGUCCAGGGCCAGGGGGUGGUAAUCAGGGACUGUUGCUGUUUUUUGUUUGUUUGUUUGUUUGUUUUUAACAGCUUGGGGUUCUCGAAGGACACUGAAGGCUGAAUUUUGCUGUCCCAAAGGGUGGACAGCAAUGACCCCUAAGUGACCCCUCUCUAGAUUUCCCUCUGGGAAGGCAGGGCCUCUACCCCACAGAGACCACCCCAUCCCCCCAGGACCAGCUCCUCACCUGCUUGCCUGGAUGCUUCUUCCCAGGAGGACCAUGCUUAUAAUGACCACCACAGCUGCCAGGGCAAGGAUGGAAUGAUUCCAGGGAGAUGCUGGGGAAGGACACACAGGACAGAGCCCUGAGGAAUGGCCAGGCACCUCUCAAGCCCGCUAACAGCUGGGGCCUGGGCUCAGACCCAGCUUACAGCAUCAACUGUCCUUUGCGUGGAGACCCUAAUCAAAGAUGGGCCCCUUGCCCUGGGGCACUCCCAGUCUAACAGGUGGGAGGGUGGAAGACAGUCUCUACUCUGGAGAAGCCCUAAUCUAAUGGAGGAGACAGUACUGCAGUUAAAUAAUAGUGGGGCAACAGGGGUGAAGGGCAGAGGCCUACGGAGGGCAGGAGACAGGUGGGCCAAGAUAAACUUCACAAUCUUCAGUUUUGCCAGCCUGGGCUGGACCUGCGGAGCACAAGGAAAAGAAAGAAGGCUGGGCUCAGUGGCUCACGCCUAUAAUCCCAGCACUUUGGGAAGCCGAGUCAGGUGGAUCACCUGAGGUCGGGAGUUCAAGACCAGCCUGGCCAACAUGGUGAAAUGCUGUCUCUACUAAAAAUACAAAAAUUAGCUGGGUGUGGUGGCAUACACUGUAAUCCCAGCUACUCAGGAGACUGAGGCAUGAGAAUCACUUGAAUCCAGGAGGCAGAGCUUGCAGUGAGCCAAGAUUGCACCACUGCACUCCAGCCUGGGCAACAGAGUGACCCUGCCUCAAAAAAAAGGCAAAAAAAAAAAAAAAAAGAAGAAGAAGAAGAAAGAAAAAAAAAGGAAAGAAAGAAGGCAGGGAGAAGGGUGGAAGGAAUGGCAACUGCCCACAGAUAAUACAUGAAGUGACUAAACUGAAUGUGGCUACUCAAGAUUUGUCCAUGCUGUACCCAAAUGAAGCAGGGUCCAGCCUCAGAGCUCUUGCAUUUGCUGUCCUCCCUCCAGGAAUGUUCCUCCCCCAAAUAAUUUGCAUACCUAAUUAUUUCCUUAGUUUCCUGCAAGUCACCUUCCUGAUGAUAAAAAUGUCACCUUUUUAGUGAGGCCUUCCUUGACCACAUUACUGCCCUUGCUGCAUACUUCCUAUUCUCUUUCUCUGUUUAAUUUUUCUUUUUAUUACUCAUCACCAACGCACUAUGCGUUUUAGUUGUUUAUUUUUAAUCCCCACUAGAAUGUACAUUCCAUGAAGGCAGAGAUUUUUGUGUUUUAUUCACUAUUGUCGCCCCAGUGCUGAGAACAGUGUCUGGUACAGAGUAGGAGCUUAAUAAAUGUGAUGAUUGGAGGGCUGCAUAAAUAAGCGACCACACCCUGAGAAAAGGAAGGGGCGGUCCAGCCAGACCCCUCUGGGUACUGAGACACCCCGACUGAUUCCCUGUCUUGGAGGAAAUGUACCGCCUGACCUGGAGGGGACGACAGUGUCAGGACCUUCAGCCAAACUCUGCUCUGUGUUGAGGGGCACACCCCCACCCCUGCCGUCAAUCUCUCACCACUUACCAUCUUCCACACGAAAAAACCAAAGCAUCUCUUCCAGCAGCUCCUGGGGUACCACAGUACCGGCUGGGUCUCCGGGAGCCCCCUCACUGUGCUCCAUGCCCCUGCUCCUGGUAGCGUGUGCAACGAGGUCCUUAGACCCCUUAGCCCCAGCAGCCCUCCUGGCCUCCUCGGUUCUGGCCCCUGGGCAGAGAAGCCGUGAAGACCCCUGGAAACAAAGCAGACAGCAUGACUGGAUAUCCCACCCGAGUUUGAUCUCCCUCUGUGCCCAAAUCCAGAUCUCCUCUGGCCCAAAGUUAUGGGACAAAAACGACCCGAACGAACCCAGGAGCACGUGGAGCCUGGAGGGGCAGAGACUGGAAGUGGGAGUGACUCAAAUAUUUAUUAAAAGCCAUCGCAUGUGUGGAGGAGCACUGUUCUGGGAGUGAGGAGGACUGAGCCACUGGCGAGUUCUGGGACCCUUGCAAAGGACAUCUCGGGUCUUCGCCUGCCUGUUCAGCGUCCGCACCUGGCUUCUACGAGCCCACAGCGCGCCCACGCGUUGCCAUAGCAACUUGUCCCUUGGGUGUCAUGCGGUAGCCAAUCACAGGCCUGUGUUUCCCCACAUGUCAAAGGCUGGGCCUAUCACGCCUCUCUCCUGGGGAUUGGCACGCCUACGACACAGAGAGGAGAAAAGGGAAAAGUGCCGGAGGGAAAGGCAGCUGCCGGCUCCUGAUGCUGAGAGGGCACCCCCUGCCCCGACCCCGAGAGCUUUUUUUUUCUUUUUCUUUUUUUUUUGGACAAGUUAGCAGAAUUGGUUUCUGUUAUUUGCAAGGGAAGAACUUGAAUCCAUGCUCUCUGGAUAAAUCCCUUACUUCGUGUAGGCCUAUUUCCAUCCCAACUAUUAAUAAUAAACUGAACCUCAGUCAAUCUCAAAA